GCAGGGAAGCCAACAGGCGAGUGGCGAAGGUGGCGGCAGCGGCGGCGGGGGCAGUCACCGGCUAGGGCGACGGCUCCGAGGCCGAGUGGCGGUCCGACAGAGUCCUCCGUGUCCUCCCCCGCAUGACCCCCUUGUUUAUUCAAUGCAAAAGAAUCCUCUCCAAUUUUACUGAGGUGGCUGACCACGUCCACGACCAAAUCCGUCUCAACUGGAAUUUGGCUGCUGACCCAGCCCCAGCCUCAGCUUUCUUGUCGGCACUAAGUGGCACAGCACUCCAUCUGUAGGGGUAAGUGUACUGGAGAGAGUUGGUUAUACAUUCUAGGAAUCUCAAAGAUGGAGUCUUGCUCUGUCACCUAGGCUGGAGUGCAUUGGUGUGAUCACGGCUCACUGCAACCUCUGCCUCCCAGGUUCAAACAAUUCUCCUGCCUCAGCCUCUUGAGUAGCUGGGAUUACAGUGAUCAGCCUUUGAGCCUUUCCCACAUUGAAGAUGGUGAAACUAGAUAUUCAUACUCUGGCUCAUCACCUCAAGCAGGAACGCUUAUAUGUAAACUCUGAGAAACAGCUCAUUCAGAGGCUCAAUGCAGAUGUACUUAAGACAGCUGAAAAGUUGUAUCGUACAGCAUGGAUUGCGAAGCAACAGAGAAUCAAUUUGGAUCGGCUUAUCAUAACCAGUGCUGAAGCUUCCCCUGCUGAAUGUUGCCAACAUGCCAAAAUUUUGGAAGAUACACAAUUUGUUGAUGGGUAUAAGCAAUUGGGAUUUCAGGAGACUGCUUAUGGAGAAUUCUUGAGUCGAUUGAGGGAAAAUCCUCGUCUUAUUGCCUCCUCUUUGGUUGCUGGAGAGAAACUUAAUCAGGAGAACACACAAAGUGUUAUUUACACAGUUUUUACCUCCCUGUAUGGCAAUUGCAUCAUGCAAGAAGAUGAAAGCUACCUCCUUCAGGUUUUGCGAUACUUGAUUGAAUUUGAACUUAAAGAAAGUGACAACCCUAGGCGACUUUUGAGGAGAGGAACUUGUGCCUUCAGCAUCUUAUUUAAACUUUUUUCUGAAGGACUGUUUUCUGCCAAACUUUUCCUCACAGCCACUUUACAUGAGCCAAUUAUGCAACUGCUUGUUGAAGAUGAAGAUCACCUGGAAACAGAUCCAAACAAGCUAAUUGAGAGGUUCUCUCCAUCUCAGCAGGAAAAACUCUUUGGAGAGAAGGGCUCAGAUAGAUUCAGGCAAAAAGUUCAAGAAAUGGUGGAGUCCAAUGAAGCAAAGCUAGUGGCUUUGGUGAACAAAUUUAUUGGUUAUCUCAAACAGAACACAUAUUGUUUUCCACAUAGUUUAAGGUGGAUCGUGUCUCAGAUGUACAAAACCCUCUCCUGUGUAGAUAGGCUGGAAGUUGGGGAGGUCAGGGCAAUGUGUACUGAUCUCCUGUUGGCCUGCUUCAUUUGUCCUGCAGUUGUCAAUCCAGAACAAUAUGGAAUAAUUUCCGAUGCUCCUAUUAAUGAAGUAGCACGAUUUAAUCUGAUGCAGGUAGGCCGCCUUUUGCAGCAGUUAGCAAUGACUGGCUCUGAAGAGGGAGAUCCCCGAACAAAGAGCAGCCUUGGAAAGUUUGACAAAAGCUGUGUUGCCGCUUUCCUUGAUGUUGUGAUUGGGGGCCGUGCAGUGGAGACCCCUCCAUUGUCUUCCGUCAAUCUUCUGGAAGGAUUGAGCAGAACUGUGGUUUAUAUAACCUACAGUCAGCUUAUUACUCUGGUGAAUUUUAUGAAGAGUGUGAUGUCUGGAGAUCAACUGAGAGAAGAUAGAAUGGCUCUUGACAAUUUAUUGGCAAACCUACCCCCGGCCAAGCCAGGAAAAAGUAGCAGUUUAGAAAUGACUCCCUACAAUACACCUCAGCUAUCUCCAGCAACCACUCCAGCAAAUAAAAAGAAUCGAUUACCUAUAGCAACUCGGAGCAGAAGCCGCACCAAUAUGCUAAUGGACCUACAUAUGGACCAUGAAGGAUCAUCUCAAGAAACCAUUCAGGAGGUGCAACCAGAAGAGGUGUUGGUCAUUUCCUUAGGUACAGGUCCCCAGCUUACUCCAGGGAUGAUGUCAGAAAAUGAGGUCCUAAACAUGCAGCUUUCGGAUGGAGGACAAGGAGAUGUCCCUGUUGAUGAAAACAAACUCCAUGGUAAACCUGAUAAAACCUUGCGCUUUUCCCUCUGCAGUGAUAAUCUGGAAGGAAUAUCUGAAGGUCCUUCAAAUCGCUCCAAUUCAGUGUCCUCCCUAGACCUAGAAGGAGAGUCUGUGUCAGAACUUGGAGCAGGACCUUCUGGCAGUAAUGGAGUUGAAGCUCUACAGCUGUUAGAACAUGAGCAAGCUACAACACAGGAUAACCUUGAUGAUAAGCUAAGGAAGUUUGAAAUUCGUGACAUGAUGGGAUUAACAGAUGAUAGGGACAUAUCAGAAACAGUGAGUGAGACCUGGAGUACAGACGUCUUGGGAAGUGACUUUGACCCUAAUAUUGAUGAAGAUCGCUUGCAAGAAAUUGCAGGUGCUGCAGCAGAGAACAUGUUAGGCAGUUUGCUGUGCCUCCCAGGUUCAGGGUCAGUGCUUCUUGACCCCUGCACUGGUUCUACCAUAUCAGAGACAACAAGUGAAGCUUGGAGUGUAGAGGUAUUGCCAAGUGACUCAGAGGCCCCAGACCUAAAGCAGGAGGAGCGUCUGCAAGAACUGGAGAGCUGUUCUGGACUGGGUAGCACAUCUGAUGAUACGGAUGUCAGGGAGGUCAGUUCCCGCCCCAGCACACCAGGCCUCAGUGUUGUGUCCGGCAUAAGUGCAACCUCUGAGGAUAUUCCCAAUAAGAUUGAAGACCUGAGAUCUGAGUGCAGCUCUGAUUUUGGGGGUAAAGAUUCUGUCACUAGUCCAGACAUGGAUGAAAUAACUCACGAUUUUCUUUAUAUACUUCAGCCAAAACAACAUUUUCAACACAUUGAAGCAGAAGCAGACAUGAGAAUCCAGCUGUCUUCUAGUGCCCACCAGCUGACCUCUCCUCCUUCUCAGUCAGAGUCUCUGCUGGCCAUGUUUGAUCCACUGUCUUCACAUGAAGGGGCUUCUGCUGUGGUAAGGCCAAAGGUUCACUAUGCUAGGCCAUCGCAUCCACCACCAGAUCCCCCAAUCCUGGAAGGAGCUGUGGGAGGAAAUGAGGCCAGGUUGCCAAACUUUGGUUCCCAUGUUUUAACUCCAGCUGAAAUGGAGGCAUUCAAGCAAAGGCAUUCUUACCCUGAGAGACUAGUUCGAAGCAGGAGCUCUGAUAUAGUAUCUUCUGUCCGGAGACCCAUGAGUGACCCCAGCUGGAACCGGCGUCCAGGAAAUGAAGAGCGAGAACUCCCUCCAGCUGCAGCCAUUGGUGCUACUUCUUUGGUGGCUGCACCUCAUUCAUCAUCUUCAUCCCCGAGUAAGGACUCCUCAAGAGGAGAGACUGAAGAACGCAAAGAUAGCGAUGAUGAGAAAUCAGACAGGAACAGACCUUGGUGGAGAAAACGUUUUGUUUCAGCCAUGCCUAAAGCUCCUAUACCAUUUAGAAAGAAAGAAAAACAAGAAAAAGACAAAGAUGAUCUGGGGCCUGACAGAUUCUCAACACUCACAGAUGAUCCCAGCCCUAGACUCAGUGCACAAGCUCAGGUGGCUGAGGAUAUUCUGGACAAAUACAGGAAUGCCAUUAAACGGACCAGCCCCAGUGAUGGAGCAAUGGCAAACUAUGAAAGUACAGAGGUUAUGGGUGAUGGUGAAAGUGCACAUGAUUCUCCCCGUGACGAAGCACUGCAGAACAUCUCGGCUGAUGAUCUCCCAGACUCUGCAAGCCAAGCAGCCCACCCGCAGGAUUCAGCUUUCUCUUACAGAGAUGCAAAAAAGAAACUGAGGCUUGCUCUUUGCUCUGCGGACUCUGUUGCCUUCCCAGUGCUGACCCAUUCAACAAGGAAUGGUUUACCAGACCACACAGACCCAGAAGACAAUGAAAUUGUAUGCUUCUUAAAAGUUCAAAUAGCUGAAGCAAUUAAUUUACAAGAUAAGAAUCUAAUGGCUCAACUUCAAGAAACAAUGCGCUGUGUGUGCCGUUUUGAUAAUAGGACUUGUAGGAAACUGCUGGCUUCGAUUGCUGAGGACUACAGAAAAAGAGCCCCAUAUAUUGCUUAUCUCACUCGUUGUCGACAAGGACUACAGACCACACAGGCUCACCUGGAAAGGCUAUUGCAAAGAGUUUUGCGGGACAAAGAAGUGGCCAAUCGAUACUUUACCACUGUCUGUGUGAGAUUACUGCUUGAGAGCAAAGAAAAGAAGAUCAGGGAAUUCAUUCAAGACUUUCAGAAACUCACCGCAGCUGACGAUAAAACUGCUCAGGUAGAAGAUUUUCUGCAGUUUCUUUAUGGUGCAAUGGCCCAGGAUGUCAUAUGGCAAAACGCGAGUGAAGAACAGCUUCAAGAUGCACAGCUGGCCAUUGAGCGAAGCGUGAUGAACCGGAUUUUCAAGCUCGCCUUCUACCCUAAUCAAGAUGGGGACAUACUUCGCGACCAGGUUCUUCAUGAACAUAUCCAGAGAUUGUCUAAAGUAGUGACUGCAAAUCACAGAGCUCUUCAGAUACCAGAGGUUUAUCUUCGAGAAGCACCAUGGCCAUCUGCACAAUCAGAAAUCAGGACAAUAAGUGCUUAUAAAACCCCCCGGGACAAAGUGCAGUGCAUCCUGAGAAUGUGCUCUACGAUUAUGAACCUCCUGAGCCUGGCCAAUGAGGACUCUGUCCCUGGAGCGGAUGACUUUGUUCCUGUGUUGGUGUUUGUGUUGAUAAAGGCAAAUCCACCCUGUUUGCUGUCUACUGUGCAGUAUAUCAGUAGCUUUUAUGCUAGCUGUCUGUCUGGAGAGGAGUCCUAUUGGUGGAUGCAGUUCACAGCAGCAGUAGAAUUCAUUAAAACCAUCGAUGACCGAAAGUGACCAAGACCAAGGCCCACCAAGGCAGCAGACUGUUAAUCAGACAAACAGAUCUCUGAGAAGGUGCAUCAGCUGCUUUGAAGGCUGAAGAUUGUUUUGUAUGAUACUGCACAGCAUCAGGCAUUUUAAAGCAGAUCUUUACUAAACAGGUUAAUGAGCUAACAAGCAGGUUCUCUCGUCUUUGGGCUCUUUCCUUUCUGAGUUGCAUAUUCUAUUUUCUUGUCCCCAAGUAGAGACUAGUACUACAAAAAGGGACCACAUUUUUCAAGUAUUUCUAAGUAUAAAAAACAAAACAAAAAUCUCUUAGGAAAUGUCUAGACCUCCAUUCUUGGAUUCCCUUUCUUUCCUUUUAUUUUAAAAAAGAACAGUACCCCUCUUUUAAGAUGCUGUCUUACAUUAAUGAGCAUCUAAUGGAAAGAAGGUAUGAGUUGCACUGAGGAUUAGAAUAGUGGUGCGUUAGUGGCAUUAUCUAUAAAUACACUCACCUAAAUUGAAAGCUAAGAAGGAAAUGUAAAUAUAAUAUAUAUUUAUAUUUGAUGUAAUAUGGACAUCUGCAGAUUCUAAUAAACAAGGACUAUUGCUGAUAGUAGGCUGUGACAUACUGUCUUGUGAAAUGGUUUCCUUGACAAAAUUUAAGCUGAGCUUAAAAGCAAAAAACAAAAAGUACACAGAAAUAUUUAUUAAAAUGUAAUACAGUUUAUUGAACUUUCUAGGUAUGGAGUUUGAUGGACAGGGCUGCCUUUAAUGAGUGUGAAGGUCACUAAGUCACUUAGACAUCUCACCGUGGAAGUUUGUGAGCCUGCAUUAGGAGAUAGACUGAUUACCAUACAUGACAUAAAAAGGAACAGUGGAUAGCUCAUACUUUAUGGUGGUUCUUCUCCUCCGAAAUAAUAUACUGCAGAAAUCCCAGACAGAGCUCCUUACAAACCUUUAAUUGUAAUAUAUUUUUGAUGAUUAUUCACAUUGAAUGCACAGACCAAGAAUUCAGUGAAUGUCAUUUUUUAAAAAACUAAUUUGUAUUGUCUGCUCUAGUGAUACAAGUUUUACUAGUGAUAAACUAUUUUAAUCAACCAUACUAUUCUUAUGGAAAAAAAUAUCUAUUUUGGCAGGUUUCUGUGCCUUUAUUUCCCUCUUCUGAAAAAAAGUCUGUGUUUUCAUAGUUUGGUUUGCAUUGUAUAUCAAUAAUUAAUCAGGAAUGGGUUUUGGUGCCUGAAAAAUUGGCCAUGGAGGCACACCAAAGCUUCAAGCACAAGUCUUGUACAUGGGCCAUCACUGUCUGGUUUCACUUCGUGUGUUUCCUAAACACAUUUAGCUGCUUUUUUAACAAACUCAGCCCCAUACUUGAGUCCCUUGUUGUUGGGAGCAUUUCCAGGCAUCUUUUAAGGGAACUGUGACAAACAGCCUCGGGCAGAUGAACACGGAGGCUCUCUGUUGUCUGUCUCUGAGAUCUUUGUGUCUGGGAAUGCCUAAAGAUUUUAUUUUUUUUUCUUUGUUUUUAUUUUAUUUUAUUUUAUUUUUUUGAGACAGAGUCUCACCCUGUUGCCCAGGCUGGAGUGCAAUGGUGCGAUCUUGGCUCACUGCAACCUCCACCUCCCAGUUCAAGUGAUUCCCCUGCCUCAGCCUCGCGAGUAGCUAGGACUACAGGCGCAUGUCACCAAGCCCGGCUAAUUUUUGUAUUUUUAGUAGAAACGGGGUUUCACCAUGUUGGCCAGGAUGAUCCUCAAUCUCCUGACCUCGUGAUCCACCCGCCUUGGCCUCCCAAAGUGCGGGAUUACAAGCGUGAACCACCCUGCCCAGCCAGAAACUAGAUUUUCUUUAUGCCUCCACCCCUUCUUAUUCAUUUACUUUACAAUACCAAAAUAACAAAUUGCAUAGGAGUGUGGGAUGUGGUUUCUGCCUUCUAGAGAGAGAUCAGAAUUAAACUAGUACUAUGAAAUGUCCUUUUGAAUGUUAGGUCAAGAAAUCCAUGUACAGAGUCGUGCACUUCAUUGGCUGUAACUGUCAAACUUGCCUUGUAUUAGAAGUUAAAUCCCAUCGUAAAUACAUCACGAGGCCAGCUGUGUGAUUUCUGAGACCUAGAUGAGAGUCCAUUUACUUCAGCCUUUGAUUCAGUAAAUGUUAAGCAGCAGAAGACUUCGAAUGGUUGAAAUUCAUUGUUACAGGAUUUAACUCAUAAACCAAUGAGAGAUUUUUUUUUUCUCUGCAAUGGUUGCUAAGUCUAUUCCAUGUUAACACUGUGGAAAUAAAUAUGAAGAUGUGGACAUUGCAUCGGGGCUCUUUUCUGUGGAAGAGAAGGUGGUGGGAUUGGGGUGAAGGGCUACACUGGAGGCAGGAGAUAGGGCUGUGCUGUGUUGGAGCCGGGGCUGAGGGUAGACCCCCCAGAGAUUUGACAUCUGUGACACCUGUGAAAUGGGUUCGGGUGCUCAUGACUCCAUAGCUGGCGGAGGAGCACAGCACAGCUGUUGCAGGGGCAGCUAAGGUUUCCUCUGAAAAUCUGUCAGGAGCAAGGACUACUUUGGCAUUAACCAUCACUGUUUGAUUUCUUGACAGGUAUGUGAGAUGGGGAGUGAUUUGAUUUUUUUUUUUUUUUUUAAUAGAAAAGAGGAAUAGUUGUUCCCCAAAUGUUUCUUCCUCCACUGCCUUCCAGUACUUUCUUUACAUGAAAGAUUAGUGUAAAAGUACAAAAUCAGCCCAGGAAACAUUCAGCAGCCACUAGUUACUACAUAGAAUUUAUAAAGUGGAUGUUAAAUGGAGAGAGAGUUGGCUCAGGUCCCCUGAAAUCUUGUAGGAUUAACUUCUCUGAGGAAAAGAAAAAUCAGGUUUGCAUUUUGUAUUAAUAUUCUGCUUUUAGAAGUAAUAGAAAUACAAGUUGAAGAUUGUCUUUACUUACAAAAUUAUAUUUUAAUUUUUUUUGAGACAUAGUCUUGCUCUGUCACCCAGUCUGGAGUGCAGUGCUGUGAUCUCGGCUCACUGUAACCACCAUCUCCCAGUCUCUAGUGAUUCUCAUGGCUCAGCCUCCCUGGUUGCUCAGAUUACAAGUGUAUGCCACCACACCCAGCUAAUUUUUGUAUUUUUUGUAGAGACAGGGUUUCGCCAUGUUGGCCAGGCUGGUCUCGAACUCCUGGCCUCAAGUGAUCCGCCUACCUCGGCUUCCCAAAGUGCUGGGAUUAUAGGCGUGAGCCACCGUGCCCAACCACAAAAUUAUAUGUAUAUAUAUUUAAACGUGUCAAACAUUUUGCUUUCUUUCUCCAUUUUAGGUAAAAUCUCAGCCACAGUAAUUGCUUUCUUCUGCUUUUUCUUUAUAAAAACCUGCUUAUGAAGGCCUUCUGAUACAGAUAGUUAAAUCGCUGUAGUAGGAGGCUCAGGUUUUCUAAGGGAUUGCAAAUGUGCUGCAUGGUUUUUCUAUUCCUAUGUCCUGGAAGCCUUUGUUUAAAGUGGGCUUUACAAAUGUGUCCCUGAGGUGCGUGAGCAAGAGAACAAUCUCAGCCCCAAUACGGGGGCUGUGUUCUUGCCGUAAGAAUCUGUAGCUGACUGGUGUGCUGAACCCGGGCACUCUUUUUCCUAUUGUUUGCCAUGGAAAUUUCCACUUUGGACCGAGUAAGGUCAACUAGGUGUUUUAAAAUUGUUUUUCUCCUAUGUGAUUGGGUGUGAAGAGGGAAAGUAGGAAUACACUCAGAAUUAUUACUGGAUUGCAUAAAAGUGAUAGAAGUGUAGUGGGGUUCACUUCCUCAAUUGGUGCUUCCUAGAUUUUUCUCUCCCAUCUCUUCCUGCUUUGUUUCUUUAAAGAAAAGGCUGUUGUCUCUCUUUUUAAAUAUUUAAGUCUAGUGAGUUUAUUUUGUACGCAAUUGCUUUAAUUUUAAGGGAAGUAAAUCUGAAACUAUCUUGAAGCCCAAAGGAUUUUUAGUAAGUGGAUUAACAGUGAUGAGGUAUUUGCGAUUACUUUAAAUGCCAAAAUGCUUGAGAACUUUGCCAGGUUAAAAAUUACUUAAUAUAUUUUAGAAUGUAGGUUAGAAAGUAGUAGGACAAGGAAUAGCUUUAUUACUCUUGAGAACACUUGGAUAAAUGAAAAUAUAGUUUGCUUCCGUGUUAAGUUGUGGUUGAGCUAUGGAGUGACCCUGGAGCUGCCGCAUCCCACAGGCCUGAGCUCAGCAAGGGUUCAAUUCAAGAGAGAUGACGUCUCCACUUGGAUAAUGGCAGACAGUGUGGGUAGCGGCCAUGCACUAGGGGAAUUCACCUCUGUCAAAUUAAUACUCUCCUGUCUACUGGAUUCUUCUUGUGCUUCACCUGGAUUAAAAAGCUGUACUGCCUCUUUUGAAACAGAUAAAACCUUUCUAUAAGUCUCAAUUAAUGAGCUUGCACAAUCUUGUAUAUGUACAGGAAACCCCUCCUGUCUCCUAAUGUGAUUAGUACUGUAAAAUAUUCUAUAAAACUGAUUAAAAGGGGAGAGCAGUUUGAUUCACAGGG